GGAGCCUGGGGAGUCCCGGGACCGACGGCGGCGGGGAUGCGGGUCUGCCUGUCCCUGGGAUGCGGGCGGGCGGGCAGGGCGAGGCCUGGAGCCCGCGGGGCGCAGGGGGCUGGACCGCGCGCUGUGAUUUUUCUGUUUAGCAGCGGGGCCUCGCCCAAGGUCGCGCGGGGCCUGUCCUGGAUAUGCUCUGGGAAGCCAGUGGCGCAGGGCAGCCGCCACCCUUCUGGAACCAGUGCCGGAGAGGGCCGGGCAGCUGGGCCUGGGGAGGGGACCGCAUGGAUGGAGCUGGGGGUAGCUGGGCGGCCUCCGGAGCCGGGAGAGUCGGCAGCUGCACUUCCGCCAGAGGGUUUCACCAUGUUGGCCAGGCUGGCCUGAACUCCUGACCUUAAGUGAUCCACUCGCCUAGGCCUUCCAAAGUGCUGGGAUUACAGGCGUGAGCCACCUCACCCAGCCUGGAGUGUCUCAUCUUCCACCACUAAAUGAAACGAUGGACCCUGAACAGAAAAAGGAACAGUGGUGGAAGAACUAGCAAAGCCCACAGCCUUGAGUUUGGCCGUGCCUGGCACGGUUGCUGUCCAGGGCUUAGAGGACAGAGGAAGAGCCCCUGAGUCUGUGCACACUCUGCCACCAUGGCCCUGCCCACCUCUGGAGCCCACAGGUGCCCAGCCCAGGCCCCUUGCUUUUGGCUAGACUCCUGCCCUACGGGGACCCCCAUGAUGGCCACUCAGGAGAUGGGCCCAGGAGGACAGGGGAGUGACUCCAGGCCAUGACCGGAAGGGGCCUGUGGCCCCUGUUCCCAGUCCCCAGGGAGACGGGAGGGUCACACGCUGUUAUGAGGAAGAGGACACCGGGCUGGCCCUGGCCCAGGGUGGCCAGCUCUGGUUUCACUACUUGGCCCCAAGCCCCUGAGGCAGGUGCAGGAGCCAGGCACGGUGAGCAGGGCCCAGUGCCCCUCAGGCUCUGGGGAAGGGGUACAGCCAGGUGGCCCAGAGCAAGGAGGUGCUGUAGACAGGUGUGACCACUUCCAGUCUCUCCCGGCCUGCUGGCCUUCAUCCUCUCCCAGAUUCCAAGGGCCACCGCUGGGAGCAUGGGGUGGACAUCGUCCCACCAGCCUCCUGGAUCCACAUCCGUAAAGACUCCAAAGUGAAGUGAGGCUGGCUUCACUCCAGCUCACAGCAGAGGAGGGGGCAGCCUCAGGGCCCAGCAACUUGCUCAGAGCGCACAGGAGUGCGCUGGGGCCGGGCCAGCCUGGCCCAGGGCCUCUGACUCUGCCCCCUGCCUGCAGGGCUGCACGGCCACUGUGUUCCACCCUCCAGCGUGGGUGGCAGUCCAGUGCGUCAUUCUGGGGCCUGAGCAGUGUGGCCAGAGGCCGGUCUGGGGUGGAGGCGACCUGGGCUGCAGGUUGUGGCUGGGGUCCUUGCUAUGCUUCUGGCAGCAGGAAUCAGAGAAGCAGUAACUGGAUCCAGCUGAGGGCCUGGCGGCCACCGAGGGUACGGGCGGCGAUCAGGUUGCGGCCGAGCCGUGAGCGUUCCACUGGACGGCUUCUACAUCCGGAAGGGCUGGGCCGGGCCGGGCCGGGAGCCCACACGGGGUUGGAGGAGGGGGGCAGGAACGAGAGAGGCCAAAAGGUGCAGGGCCGUGAAGAGGGGCGCUGGGCCCACGCUAUGAGGAAAAGGGGAUCAACCCUGCCCUCCAGCCCCGUAGGCCCUCAGGCCCUCGGGCUCUGGGCUCUGUGCAAUCCGGGAGUGGCUGAAAUCCAAGCUGAGGGUAAUGAAAGGUGCUGCUCCUAAGCCGCACGUCUCUGAUCCGCCCUCCCCGCCCGCCCUCUGCUGCCCGCGGGCCCUCUAAGAGCUGCCCAGGCUGCUGCCGCGGGUCAGAGGCGGGUCAGAGCAGGCAGGGGGUUCGUGACGCCGGCUGGGUCUGGGGGCUGUGGGCCAGCCGAGCCGACCCGGGCUUCUGGGGGACCGCGGGGGCCGUGAGCACUCAGAGGGCGCAUCCCAGGCCCCUCCGGGGACCCGGCCAGCCUGAAGAUGCCGACGAACGGCCUGCACCAGGUGCUGAAGAUCCAGUUUGGCCUCGUCAACGACACUGACCGCUACCUGACAGCUGAGAGCUUCGGCUUCAAGGUCAAUGCCUCGGCACCCAGCCUCAAGAGGAAGCAGACCUGGGUGCUGGAACCCGACCCAGGACAAGGCACGGCUGUGCUGCUCCGCAGCAGCCACCUGGGCCGCUACCUGUCGGCAGAAGAGGACGGGCGCGUGGCCUGUGAGGCAGAGCAGCCGGGCCGUGACUGCCGCUUCCUGGUCCUGCCGCAGCCAGAUGGGCGCUGGGUGCUGCGGUCCGAGCCGCACGGCCGCUUCUUCGGAGGCACCGAGGACCAGCUGUCCUGCUUCGCCACAGCCGUUUCCCCGGCCGAGCUGUGGACCGUGCACCUGGCCAUCCACCCGCAGGCCCACCUGCUGAGCGUGAGCCGGCGGCGCUACGUGCACCUGUGCCCGCGGGAGGACGAGAUGGCCGCAGACGGAGACAAGCCCUGGGGCGUGGACGCCCUCCUCACCCUCAUCUUCCGGAGCCGACGGUACUGCCUCAAGUCCUGUGACAGCCGCUACCUGCGCAGCGACGGCCGUCUGGUCUGGGAGCCUGAGCCCCGUGCCUGCUACACGCUGGAGUUCAAGGCGGGCAAGCUGGCCUUCAAGGACUGCGACGGCCACUACCUGGCACCCGUGGGGCCCGCAGGCACCCUCAAGGCCGGCCGAAACACGCGACCUGGCAAGGAUGAGCUCUUUGAUCUGGAGGAGAGUCACCCACAGGUGGUGCUGGUGGCUGCCAACCACCGCUACGUCUCUGUGCGGCAAGGGGUCAACGUCUCAGCCAAUCAGGAUGAUGAACUAGACCACGAGACCUUCCUGAUGCAAAUUGACCAGGAGACAAAGAAGUGCACCUUCUAUUCCAGCACUGGGGGCUACUGGACCCUGGUCACCCAUGGGGGCAUUCACGCCACAGCCACACAAGUUUCUGCCAACACCAUGUUUGAGAUGGAGUGGCGUGGCCGGCGGGUAGCACUCAAAGCCAGCAACGGGCGCUACGUGUGCAUGAAGAAGAAUGGGCAGCUGGCGGCUAUCAGCGAUUUUGUCGGGCCCCCACCCCGCCCGGCCUGGACAGGGAAGGUGGCGGGAGGGGCAGCGCAGCAGACGCUCUCCCCGCCAGGCAAGGACGAAGAGUUCACCCUCAAGCUCAUCAACCGGCCCAUCCUGGUGCUGCGCGGCCUGGACGGCUUCGUCUGCCACCACCGCGGCUCCAACCAGCUGGACACCAACCGCUCCGUCUACGACGUCUUCCACCUGAGCUUCAGCGACGGCGCCUACCGGAUCCGAGGCCGCGACGGAGGGUUCUGGUACACGGGCAGCCACGGCAGCGUGUGCAGCGACGGCGAACGCGCCGAGGACUUCGUCUUCGAGUUCCGUGAGCGCGGCCGCCUGGCCAUCCGCGCCCGGAGCGGCAAGUACCUGCGCGGCGGCGCCUCGGGCCUGCUGCGGGCCGAUGCCGACGCCCCGGCCGGGACCGCGCUUUGGGAGUACUGAGGCCGCGCCCAGACCAGCCUGUCGCGCAUUAAAACCGUGUCUCUCCCGCA